AAACCCGGGCCCGUUGCAUCCGCUGGGUGUAGCCGUGGGGAUGGCAGGUUCGGGGAGGCUGGUCCUACGGCCCUGGAUUCGGGAGCUGAUUCUGGGGUCAGAGACACCCUCCAGUCCACGAGCCGGGCAGCUGCUUGAGGUACUACAGGACGCCGAGGCCGCGGUCGCGGGCCCAUCCCACGCCCCUGAUACGUCCGACGUCGGGGCCACGCUGCUUGUGUCUGACGGGACCCACAGUGUCCGAUGCCUGGUGACGCGGGAGGCCCUGGACACCUCGGACUGGGAGGAGAAGGAGUUCGGCUUCCGCGGGACAGAGGGCCGGCUGCUGCUGCUGCAGGACUGCGGGGUUCAUGUCCAGGUCGCUGAGGGCGGCGCGCCCGCAGAGUUCUAUCUCCAGGUGGACCGCUUCAGCCUGCUGCCCACGGAGCAGCCCCGGCUACGGGUGCCUGGUUGCAACCAAGACUUAGAUGUUCAGAAAAAGCUCUAUGACUGCCUUGAGGAGCACCUUUCAGAGUCCACCUCGUCCAAUGCAGGCCUAUCACUGUCCCAGCUUCUGGAUGAAAUGCGGGAGGACCAGGAGCAUCAGGGGGCACUCGUGUGCCUGGCUGAAAGCUGCCUGACACUGGAGGGCCCUUGCACAGCACCCCCUGUCACCCACUGGGCUGCCUCACGAUGCAAGGCCACGGGAGAAGCUGUGUACACUGUCCCCAGCUCAAUGCUGUGCAUCUCUGAGAAUGACCAGCUAAUUCUGAGCUCUCUAGGCCCCUGUCAGAGGACACAGGGCCCUGAGCUGCCCCCACCAGACCCGGCUCUGCAGGACCUAUCUCUGACCCUCAUAGCCUCUCCUCCUUCCUCACCCAGUUCCUCAGGAACCCCGGCCUUACCCGGCCACAUGUCAUCCGAGGAAAGUGGUACCAGCAUCAGCCUUCUGCCUGCCCUGUCCUUGGCUGCUCCAGACCCAGGGCAGAGAAGCAGCUCCCAGCCCUCACCAGCCAUCUGCUCAGCCCCUGCCACCCUGACCCCCAGGUCCCCACACGCCAGCCGUACCCCCAGCUCCCCACUCCAGAGCUGCACUCCCAGUCUCUCACCCCGUAGCCAUGUCCCCAGUCCACACCAGGCUCUUGUGACCAGGCCCCAGAAACCUAGCCUGGAGUUCAAGGAGUUUGUAGGGUUGCCCUGCAAGAAUCGGCCGCCUUUUCCCAGGACCGGAGCUACCAGGGGAGCCCAGGAGCCCUGCUCUGUCUGGGAACCCCCAAAGAGGCAUCGUGAUGGUUCUGCCUUCCAGUAUGAGUAUGAGCCACCCUGCACGUCCCUCUGUGCUCGGGUCCAAGCUGUCAGGCUUCCUCCCCAGCUCAUGGCCUGGGCCUUGCACUUUCUGAUGGAUGCACAGCCAGGGUCUGAGCCAACUCCGAUGUGAGACGUCACGCAGGACAGAUACCGCUCCACACUCUGCUUCCUUUGAGUUUUUUAAUAAAAUAAUCUCAUGCGGCAGGAGAGGAGAGGAUCAGGGA